AGGCCCUGGAGUGGGCACCCAGAGGGAAGACAGGUUGGCUAAUUUCCUGGAGCCCCUAAGGGUGCAAGGGGGAAGAACACCCACCCGCAAAGCCCCGUAGGGCUGGACCCUACGUUAGCCUGCCCUGCUCGGGGUUGGCGAUGCUGGAGGUGGGCCUUGGACCAGAGAAAAUGCUUUAAUUAGGUGACAAGCGGGCAGAGGCCUUUGUCUCUGGCGCCGGCAGCCACGGCCCCCGCUGACGGCGUGGGAAACAGACCCUGUUCCACUCCGGUCUCCAGCCUUGGAAUGGUUGCCUUCGUGCAGUGCAGGAGGACGCGGCAGAGGGCGGACGAUCGCUCCACUCGCCGGGACCAGGUGCGGGGGCCCUGCCCAGCCGCUGGGGCGUGGCCAGGCUCGAAGCACCCAGGUGUCGGGGGCCGACUCUAAGCCCUGGCACCGGAAGAGAGAGGGCGGCGGAUUGGACCUCCCGGCUCCAGCAUUGCAACUGGGCGCUCCGUCUCCUGGUCCACGCAAUGAUGCUGCGGCUGCUCAGAAGCCAGGUAGCCUGCCCUGGGUGAAGCCUUCGCGCAGGUCAAUGACGGGGCGGAGGGGCAGGGCGCGGUCCCCUGCAUCCCCGAUCUGGGGAGCGGUGGGCCCAGGGGCCAUCGCCUUAGCCCCUGGCGCUGGGGCUCGGCGCCAAGUGACGGGCGGGGCUCCACCUUCCAGCCAUCCGCCCGGCCCGGGAGGGCGGACGCUGCGAGACUCCCGGCCGCGCCCUCUCCUUCCUCUCCUCCCCAAGCCCUCGCUGCCAGUCCGGACAGGCUGCGCGGAGGGGAGGGCUGCCGGGCCGGAUAGCCGGACGCCUGGCGUUCCAGGGGCGGCCGGAUGUGGCCUGCCUUUGCGGAGGGUGCGCUCCGGCCACGAAAAGCGGACUGUGGAUCUGCCACCUGCAAGCAGCUCGGCCAUGUGGCUCCGGAGCCAUCGUCAGCUCUGCCUGGCCUUCCUGCUAGUCUGUGUCCUCUCUGUAAUCUUCUUCCUCCAUAUCCAUCAAGACAGCUUUCCACAUGGCCUAGGCCUGUCGAUCCUGUGUCCAGACCGCCGCCUGGUGACACCCCCAGUGGCCAUCUUCUGCCUGCCGGGUACUGCGAUGGGCCCCAACGCCUCCUCUUCCUGUCCCCAGCACCCUGCUUCCCUCUCCGGCACCUGGACUGUCUACCCCAAUGGCCGGUUUGGUAAUCAGAUGGGACAGUAUGCCACGCUGCUGGCUCUGGCCCAGCUCAACGGCCGCCGGGCCUUUAUCCUGCCUGCCAUGCAUGCCGCCCUGGCCCCGGUAUUCCGCAUCACCCUGCCCGUGCUGGCCCCAGAAGUGGACAGCCGCACGCCGUGGCGGGAGCUGCAGCUUCACGACUGGAUGUCGGAGGAGUACGCGGACUUGAGAGAUCCUUUCCUGAAGCUCUCUGGCUUCCCCUGCUCUUGGACUUUCUUCCACCAUCUCCGGGAACAGAUCCGCAGAGAGUUCACCCUGCACGACCACCUUCGGGAAGAGGCGCAGAGUGUGCUGGGUCAGCUCCGCCUGGGCCGCACAGGGGACCGCCCGCGCACCUUUGUCGGCGUCCACGUGCGCCGUGGGGACUAUCUGCAGGUUAUGCCUCAGCGCUGGAAGGGUGUGGUGGGCGACAGCGCCUACCUCCGGCAGGCCAUGGACUGGUUCCGGGCACGGCACGAAGCCCCCGUUUUCGUGGUCACCAGCAACGGCAUGGAGUGGUGUAAAGAAAACAUCGACACCUCCCAGGGCGAUGUGACGUUUGCUGGCGAUGGACAGGAGGCUACACCGUGGAAAGACUUUGCCCUGCUCACACAGUGCAACCACACCAUUAUGACCAUUGGCACCUUCGGCUUCUGGGCUGCCUACCUGGCUGGCGGAGACACUGUCUACCUGGCCAACUUCACCCUGCCAGACUCUGAGUUCCUGAAGAUCUUUAAGCCGGAGGCGGCCUUCCUGCCCGAGUGGGUGGGCAUUAAUGCAGACUUGUCUCCACUCUGGACAUUGGCUAAGCCUUGAGAGCCAGGGAGACUUUCUGAAGUAGCCUGAUCUUUCUAGAGCCAGCAGUACGUGGCUUCAGAGGCCUGGCAUCUUCUGGAGAAGCUUGUGGUGUUCCUGAAGCAAAUGGGUGCCCGUAUCCAGAGUGAUUCUAGUUGGGAGAGUUGGAGAGAAGGGGGACGUUUCUGGAACUGUCUGAAUAUUCUAGAACUAGCAAAACAUCUUUUCCUGAUGGCUGGCAGGCAGUUCUAGAAGCCACAGUGCCCACCUGCUCUUCCCAGCCCAUAUCUACAGUACUUCCAGAUGGCUGCCCCCAGGAAUGGGGAACUCUCCCUCUGGUCUACUCUAGAAGAGGGGUUACUUCUCCCCUGGGUCCUCCAAAGACUGAAGGAGCAUAUGAUUGCUCCAGAGCAAGCAUUCACCAAGUCCCCUUCUGUGUUUCUGGAGUGAUUCUAGAGGGAGACUUGUUCUAGAGAGGACCAGGUUUGAUGCCUGUGAAGAACCCUGCAGGGCCCUUAUGGACAGGAUGGGGUUCUGGAAAUCCAGAUAACUAAGGUGAAGAAUCUUUUUAGUUUUUUUUUUUUUUUUUUGGAGACAGGGUCUCGCUCUGUUGCCCAGGCUGGAGUGCAGUGGCGUGAUCUUGGCUCACUGCAACUUCCGCCUCCUGUGUUCAAGCGAUUCUCCUGUCUCAGCCUCCUGAGUAGAUGGGACUACAGGCACAGGCCAUUAUGCCUGGCUAAUUUUUGUAUUUUUAGUAGAGACAGGGUUUCACCAUGUUGGCCAGGAUGGUCUCGAUCUCCUGACCUUGUCAUCCACCUGUCUUGGCCUCCCAAAGUGCUGGGAUUACUGGCAUGAGCCACUGUGCCCAGCCCGGAUAUUUUUUUUUUAAUUAUUUAUUUAUUUAUUUAUUUAUUGAGACGGAGUCUUGCUCUGUAGCCCAGGCCAGAGUGCAGUGGCGCGAUCUCAGCUCACUGCAAGCUCUGCCUCCCGGGUUCAUGCCAUUCUGCCUCAGCCUCCUGAGUAGCUGGGACUACAGGCGCCCGCCACCACGCCCGGCUAAUUUUUUUUGUAUUUUUAGUAGAGACGGGGUUUCAUCGUGUUAACCAGGAUGGUCUCGAUCUCCUGACCUCGUGAUCUGCCCACCUCGGCCUCCCACAGUGCUGGGAUUACCGGCGUGAGCCACCAUGCCUGGCCCGGAUAAUUUUUUUUAAUUUUUGUAGAGACGAGGUCUUGUGAUAUUGCCCAGGCUGUUCUUCAACUCCUGGGCUCAAGCAGUCCUCCCACCUUGGCCUCCCAGAAUGCUGGGUUUAUAGAUGUGAGCCAGCACACCGGGCCAAGUGAAGAAUCUAAUGAAUGUGCAACCUAAUUGUAGCAUCUAAUGAAUGUUCCACCAUUGCUGGAAAAAUUGAGAUGGAAAACAAACCAUCUCUAGUUGGCCAGCGUCUUGCUCUGUUCACAGUCUCUGGAAAAGCUGGGGUAGUUGGUGAGCAGAGCGGGACUCUGUCCAACAAGCCCCACAGCCCCUCAAAGACUUUUUUUUGUUUGUUUUGAGCAGACAGGCUAAAAUGUGAACGUGGGGUGAGGGAUCACUGCCAAAAUGGUACAGCUUCUGGAGCAGAACUUUCCAGGGAUCCAGGGACACUUUUUUUUAAAGCUCAUAAACUGCCAAGAGCUCCAUAUAUUGGGUGUGAGUUCAGGUUGCCUCUCACAAUGAAGGAAGUUGGUCUUUGUCUGCAGGUGGGCUGCUGAGGGUCUGGGAUCUGUUUUCUGGAAGUGUGCAGGUAUAAACACACCCUCUGUGCUUGUGACAAACUGGCAGGUACCGUGCUCAUUGCUAACCACUGUCUGUCCCUGAACUCCCAGAACCACUACAUCUGGCUUUGGGCAGGUCUGAGAUAAAACGAUCUAAAGGUAGGCAGACCCUGGACCCAGCCUCAGAUCCAGGCAGGAGCACGAGGUCUGGCCAAGGUGGACGGGGUUGUCGAGAUCUCAGGAGCCCCUUGCUGUUUUUUGGAGGGUGAAAGAAGAAACCUUAAACAUAGUCAGCUCUGAUCACAUCCCCUGUCUACUCAUCCAGACCCCAUGCCUGUAGGCUUAUCAGGGAGUUACAGUUACAAUUGUUACAGUACUGUUCCCAACUCAGCUGCCACGGGUGAGAGAGCAGGAGGUAUGAAUUAAAAGUCUACAGCACUAA